AUUCUGACUGCAGUCUGUGGUUCUGAUUCCAUACCAGAGGAGACGGGAUUUCACCAUGUUGUCCAGGCUGGUCUGAAACUCCUGACAUCAGGGCUCAGGAUGCUGUUGCUGGGAGCUGUUCUACUGCUAUUAGCUCUGCCCGGUCAUGACCAGGAAACCACGACUCAAGGGCCCGGAGUCCUGCUUCCCCUGCCCAAGGGGGCCUGCACAGGUUGGAUGGCGGGCAUCCCAGGGCAUCCGGGCCAUAAUGGGGCCCCAGGCCGUGAUGGCAGAGAUGGCACCCCUGGUGAGAAGGGUGAGAAAGGAGAUCCAGGUCUUAUUGGUCCUAAGGGAGACAUCGGUGAAACCGGAGUACCCGGGGCUGAAGGUCCCCGAGGCUUUCCGGGAAUCCAAGGCAGGAAAGGAGAACCUGGAGAAGGUGCCUAUGUAUACCGCUCAGCAUUCAGUGUGGGAUUGGAGACUUACGUUACUAUCCCCAACAUGCCCAUUCGCUUUACCAAGAUCUUCUACAAUCAGCAAAACCACUAUGAUGGCUCCACUGGUAAAUUCCACUGCAACAUUCCUGGGCUGUACUACUUUGCCUACCACAUCACAGUCUAUAUGAAGGAUGUGAAGGUCAGCCUCUUCAAGAAGGACAAGGCUAUGCUCUUCACCUAUGAUCAGUACCAGGAAAAUAAUGUGGACCAGGCCUCCGGCUCUGUGCUCCUGCAUCUGGAGGUGGGCGACCAAGUCUGGCUCCAGGUGUAUGGGGAAGGAGAGCGUAAUGGACUCUAUGCUGAUAAUGACAAUGACUCCACCUUCACAGGCUUUCUUCUCUACCAUGACACCAACUGAUCACCACUAACUCAGAGCCUCCUCCAGGCCAAACAGCCCCAAAGUCAAUUAAAGGCUUUCAGUACGGUUAGGAAGUUGAUUAUUAUUUAGUUGGAGGCCUUUAGAUAUUAUUCAUUCAUUUACUCAUUCAUUUAUUCAUUCAUUCAUCGAGUAACUUUAAAAAAAUCAUAUGCUAUGUUCCCAGUCCUGGGGAGCUUCACAAACAUGACCAGAUAACUGACUAGAAAGAAGUAGUUGACAGUGCUAUUUUGUGCCCACUGUCUCUCCUGAUGCUCAUAUCAAUCCUAUAAGGCACAGGGAACAAGCAUUCUCCUGUUUUUACAGAUUGUAUCCUGAGGCUGAGAGAGUUAAGUGAAUGUCUAAGGUCACACAGUAUUAAGUGACAGUGCUAGAAAUCAAACCCAGAGCUGUGGACUUUGUUCACUAGACUGUGCCCUUUUAUAGAGGUACAUGUUCUCUUUGGAGUGUUGGUAGGUGUCUGUUUCCCACCUCACCUGAGAGCCAUUGAAUUUGCCUUCCUCAUGAAUUAAAACCUCCCCCAAGCAGAGCUUCCUCAGAGAAAGUGGUUCUAUGAUGACGUCCUGUCUUGGAAGGACUACUACUCAAUGGCCCCUGCACUACUCUACUUCCUCUUACCUAUGUCCCUUCUCAUGCCUUUCCCUCCAACGGGGAAAGCCAACUCCAUCUCUAAGUGCCGAACUCAUCCCUGUUCCUCAAGGCCACCUGGCCAGGAGCUUCUCUGAUGUGAUAUCCACUUUUUUUUUUUUUGAGAUGGAGUCUCACUCUGUCACCCAGGCUGGAGUACAGUGACACGACCUCGGCUCACUGCAGCCUCCUUCUCCUGGGUCCAAGCAAUUAUUGUGCCUCAGCCUCCCGAGUAGCUGAGACUUCAGGUGCAUUCCACCACACAUGGCUAAUUUUUGUAUUUUUAGUAGAAAUGGGGUUUCGUCAUGUUGGCCAGGCUGGUCUCGAACUCCUGGCCUAGGUGAUCCACCCGCCUCGACCUCCCAAAGUGCUGGGAUUACAGGCAUGAGCCACCAUGCCCAGUCGAUAUCUCACUUUUUAUUUUGCCAUGGAUGAGAGUCCUGGGUGUGAGGAACACCUCCCACCAGGCUAGAGGCAACUGCCCAGGAAGGACUGUGCUUCCGUCACCUCUAAAUCCCUUGCAGAUCCUUGAUAAAUGCCUCAUGAAGACCAAUCUCUUGAAUCCCAUAUCUACCCAGAAUUAACUCCAUUCCAGUCUCUGCAUGUAAUCAGUUUUAUCCACAGAAACAUUUUCAUUUUAGGAAAUCCCUGGUUUUAAGUAUCAAUCCUUGUUCAGCUGGACAAUAUGAAUCUUUUCCACUGAAGUUAGGGAUGACUGUGAUUUUCAGAACACGUCCAGAAUUUUUCAUCAAGAAGGUAGCUUGAGCCUGAAAUGCAAAACCCAUGGAGGAAUUCUGAAGCCAUUGUCUCCUUGAGUACCAACAGGGUCAGGGAAGACUGGGCCUCCUGAAUUUAUUAUUGUUCUUUAAGAAUUACAGGUUGAGGUAGUUGAUGGUGGUAAACAUUCUCUCAGGAGACAAUAACUCCAGUGAUGUUCUUCAAAGAUUUUAGCAAAAACAGAGUAAAUAGCAUUCUCUAUCAAUAUAUAAAUUUAAAAAACUAUCUUUUUGCUUACAGUUUUAAAUUCUGAACAAUUCUCUCUUAUAUGUGUAUUGCUAAUCAUUAAGGUAUUAUUUUUUCCACAUAUAAAGCUUUGUCUUUUUGUUGUUGUUGUUGUUUUUAAGAUGGAGUUUCCCUCUGUUGCCAGGCUAGAGUGCAGUGGCAUGAUCUCGGCUUACUGCAACCUUUGCCUCCCAGGUUCAAGCGAUUCUUCUGCCUCAGCCUCCCGAGUAGCUGGGACCACAGGUGCCUACCACCAUGCCAGGCUAAUUUUUGUAUUUUUAGUAAAGACAGGGUUUCACCAUAUUGGCCAGGCUGGUCUCGAACUCCUGACCUUGUGAUCUGCCCGCCUCCAUUUUUGUUGUUAUUUUUUGAGAAAGAUAGAUAUGAGGUUUAGAGAGGGAUGAAGAGGUGAGAGUAAGCCUUGUGUUAGUCAGAACUCUGUGUUGUGAAUGUCAUUCACAACAGAAAACCCAAAAUAUUAUGCAAACUACUGUAAGCAAGAAAAAUAAAGGAAAAAUGGAAACAUUUAUUCCUUUGCAUAAUAGAAAUUACCAGAGUUGUUCUGUCUUUAGAUAAGGUUUGAACCAAAGCUCAAAACAAUCAAGACCCUUUUCUGUAUGUCCUUCUGUUCUGCCUUCCGCAGUGUAGGCUUUACCCUCAGGUGCUACACAGUAUAGUUCUAGGGUUUCCCUCCCGAUAUCAAAAAGACUGUGGCCUGCCCAGCUCUCGUAUCCCCAAGCCACACCAUCUGGCUAAAUGGACAUCAUGUUUUCUGGUGAUGCCCAAAGAGGAGAGAGGAAGCUCUCUUUCCCAGAUGCCCCAGCAAGUGUAACCUUGCAUCUCAUUGCUCUGGCUGAGUUGUGUGCCUGUUUCUGACCAAUCACUGAGUCAGGAGGAUGAAAUAUUCAUAUUGACUUAAUUGCAGCUUAAGUUAGGGGUAUGUAGAGGUAUUUUCCCUAAAGCAAAAUUGGGACACUGUUAUCAGAAAUAGGAGAGUGGAUGAUAGAUGCAAAAUAAUACCUGUCCACAACAAACUCUUAAUGCUGUGUUUGAGCUUUCAUGAGUUUCCCAGAGAGACAUAGCUGGAAAAUUCCUAUUGAUUUUCUCUAAAAUUUCAACAAGUAGCUAAAGUCUGGCUAUGCUCACAGUCUCACAUCUGGUUGGGGUGGGCUCCUUACAGAACACGCUUUCACAGUUACCCUAAACUCUCUGGGGCAGGGUUAUUCCUUUGUGGAACCAGAGGCACAGAGAGAGUCAACUGAGGCCAAAAGAGGCCUGAGAGAAACUGAGGUCAAGAUUUCAGGAUUAAUGGUCCUGUGAUGCUUUGAAGUACAAUUGUGGAUUUGUCCAAUUCUCUUUAGUUCUGUCAGCUUUUGCUUCAUAUAUUUUAGCGCUCUAUUAUUAGAUAUAUACAUGUUUAGUAUUAUGUCUUAUUGGUGCAUUUACUCUCUUAUCAUUAUGUAAUGUCCUUCUUUAUCUGUGAUAAUUUUCUGUGUUCUGAAGUCUACUUUGUCUAAAAAUAACAUACGCACUCAACUUCCUUUUCUUUCUUCCUUCCUUUCUUUCUUCCUUCCUUUCUUUCUCUCUCUCUCUCUUUCCUUCCUUCCUUCCUCCUUUUCUUUCUCUCUCUCUCUCUCUCUCUUUUUUUGACAGACUCUCGUUCUGUGGCCCUGGCUGGAGUUCAGUGGUGUGAUCUUGGCUCACUGCUACCUCUACCAUGAGCAAUUCUCCUGCCUCAGCCUCCCAAGUAGCUGGAACUACAGGCUCAUGCCACUGCGCCCAGCUAAUUUUUGUAUUUUUCGUAGAGACGGGGUUUCACCACAUUCGUCAGGUUGGUUUCAAACUCCUGACUUUGUGAUCCACCCGCCUCGGCCUCCCAAAGUGCUGGGAUUACAGGCAUGAGCCAUCACACCUGGUCAACUUUCUUUUGAUUAGUGUUUUUGUGGUAUAUCUUUUUCCAUCAUGUUACUUUAAAUAUAUCUAUAUUAUUGUAUUUAAAAUGUGUUUCUUACAGACUGCAUGUAGUUGGGUAUAAUUUUUAUCCAGUCUAAAAAUAUCUGUCUUUUAAUUGGUGUUUAGACAAUUUAUAUUUAAUAAAAUUGUUGAAUUUAA